AGCUGCAGCAGAAGAGCGGAAAUGUCAAACGUGGAGGGCUGUGCCUGGCUGCUCCUGAGAAAACUGGAAGAUGGUGUGCCAUGUCAGAUCACGAGGCCACGAAGUGCACCAGUUUCCGAGACAAUAUGAAAAAAGUGUUUCCAGCAGAUGGUCCCCUUGUCACCUGCGUGGAGAGAGCGUCUUCCCUUGAGUACAUUAAAGCCAUCACAGAACAUUUUGGAAAAGACAAGUCGUCAGAAUUUCAGCUCUUUGGCUCUCCUCAUGAGACAGAUCUGCUGUUUACUGAUGCUGCCCAUGGGUUUUUAAUGGUCCCACCUAAGAUAGAUGCCAAGCUGUACCUGGGAUAUGAGUAUUUUUCCGCGACUCAGGAUCCAAAAAGAGUCACUCCAGGAGGGGUUCCACUGCCACCAUUUAACUGAAGAAAAAUUUAGGCUCCUAGAUGAUAAGGACGUGUCUGAGGUCACCUAAGAAGGACAAGACGGACCUUCCAUCUGCCAUGUUGACUCCCAACUUCUCCAAGUUUGAAUUUGUAGAGACCUGAUCUACAACACAGAGAAAAGGCUAUUAUGUCAUGGCUGUGGUUAAGAAAUCAGAUGCUGAUGUCACCUGGAACUCUCUUUGAGGCAAGAAGUCCUGCCACACUGCAGUUGGCACUUCUGCAAGCUGGAACAUCCCCAUGGGCUUAAUAUACAAUCAAACCGGGUCCUGUAAAUGUGAUGAUUUCUUCAGUCGCAGUUGUGCCCCUGGGUCUAAUCCGGAUUCCCCUCUCUGUGCUCUGUGUGGUGGCAGGUGCAAUCCUGCCCACAUAUGGGCUUACAACAGCCAGGAGAGAUACUACGGCUCCAGUGGGGCUUUCAGGGCACUCUCCUGCAGACCCAGAUGAUUUAGGGCACCUUAGGGCACCUAGGGAGAAGCAAGAAUGAUGGCGGCAGAGUCACAACUCUAGUUCUACUUUUGCCACUUUCUUCUGUGUGACUGUGGACAAGUCAAGAAUCCAUCAGAGCCUUGGUUUAAAAUCACAGGGGGGACACCAGACACCUCACUUCUUACACUUGGCUGGGCUGUGUCUGGCUGUCCCUGAUAAAACUGUGAGAUGGUGUGCAGUGUCGGAGCAUGAGGCCACUAAGUGCCAGAGUUUCCGCGACCAUAUGAAAAGCGUCAUUCCAUCCGAUGGUCCCAGUGUUGCUUGUGUGAAGAAAGCCUCCUACCUUGAUUGCAUCAGGGCCAUUGCGGCAAACGAAGCGGAUGCUGUGACACUGGAUGCAGGUUUGGUGUAUGAUGCUUACCUGGCUCCCAAUAACCUGAAGCCUGUGGUGGCAGAGUUCUAUGGGUCAAAAGAGGAUCCACAGACUUUCUAUUAUGCUGUUGCUGUGGUGAAGAAGGAUAGUGGCUUCCAGAUGAACCAGCUUCGAGGCAAGAAGUCCUGCCACACGGGUCUAGGCAGGUCCGCUGGGUGGAACAUCCCCAUAGGCUUACUUUACUGUGACUUACCUGAGCCACGUAAACCUCUUGAGAAAGCAGUGGCCAAUUUCUUCUCGGGCAGCUGUGCCCCUUGUGCGGAUGGGACGGACUUCCCCCAGCUGUGUCAACUGUGUCCAGGGUGUGGCUGCUCCACCCUUAACCAAUACUUCGGCUACUCGGGAGCCUUCAAGUGUCUGAAGGAUGGUGCUGGGGAUGUGGCCUUUGUCAAGCACUCGACUAUAUUUGAGAACUUGGCAAACAAGGCUGACAGGGACCAGUAUGAGCUGCUUUGCCUGGACAACACCCGGAAGCCGGUAGAUGAAUACAAGGACUGCCACUUGGCCCAGGUCCCUUCUCAUACCGUCGUGGCCCGAAGUAUGGGCGGCAAGGAGGACUUGAUCUGGGAGCUUCUCAACCAGGCCCAGGAACAUUUUGGCAAAGACAAAUCAAAAGAAUUCCAACUAUUCAGCUCUCCUCAUGGGAAGGACCUGCUGUUUAAGGACUCUGCCCACGGGUUUUUAAAAGUCCCCCCCAGGAUGGAUGCCAAGAUGUACCUGGGCUAUGAGUAUGUCACUGCCAUCCGGAAUCUACGGGAAGGCACAUGCCCAGAAGCCCCAACAGAUGAAUGCAAGCCUGUGAAGUGGUGUGCGCUGAGCCACCACGAGAGGCUCAAGUGUGAUGAGUGGAGUGUUAACAGUGUAGGGAAAAUAGAGUGUGUAUCAGCAGAGACCACCGAAGACUGCAUCGCCAAGAUCAUGAAUGGAGAAGCUGAUGCCAUGAGCUUGGAUGGAGGGUUUGUCUACAUAGCGGGCAAGUGUGGUCUGGUGCCUGUCUUGGCAGAAAACUACAAUAAGAGCGAUAAUUGUGAGGAUACACCAGAGGCAGGGUAUUUUGCUAUAGCAGUGGUGAAGAAAUCAGCUUCUGACCUCACCUGGGACAAUCUGAAAGGCAAGAAGUCCUGCCAUACGGCAGUUGGCAGAACCGCUGGCUGGAACAUCCCCAUGGGCCUGCUCUACAAUAAGAUCAACCACUGCAGAUUUGAUGAAUUUUUCAGUGAAGGUUGUGCCCCUGGGUCUAAGAAAGACUCCAGUCUCUGUAAGCUGUGUAUGGGCUCAGGCCUAAACCUGUGUGAACCCAACAACAAAGAGGGAUACUACGGCUACACAGGCGCUUUCAGGUGUCUGGUUGAGAAGGGAGAUGUGGCCUUUGUGAAACACCAGACUGUCCCACAGAACACUGGGGGAAAAAACCCUGAUCCAUGGGCUAAGAAUCUGAAUGAAAAAGACUAUGAGUUGCUGUGCCUUGAUGGUACCAGGAAACCUGUGGAGGAGUAUGCGAACUGCCACCUGGCCAGAGCCCCGAAUCACGCUGUGGUCACACGGAAAGAUAAGGAAGCUUGCGUCCACAAGAUAUUACGUCAACAGCAGCACCUAUUUGGAAGCAACGUAACUGACUGCUCGGGCAACUUUUGUUUGUUCCGGUCGGAAACCAAGGACCUUCUGUUCAGAGAUGACACAGUAUGUUUGGCCAAACUUCAUGACAGAAACACAUAUGAAAAAUACUUAGGAGAAGAAUAUGUCAAGGCUGUUGGUAACCUGAGAAAAUGCUCCACCUCAUCACUCCUGGAAGCCUGCACUUUCCGUAGACCUUAAAAUCUCAGAGGUAGGGCUGCCACCAAGGUGAAGAUGGGAACGCAGAUGAUCCAUGAGUUUGCCCUGGUUUCACUGGCCCAAGUGGUUUGUGCUAACCACGUCUGUCUUCACAGCUCUGUGUUGCCAUGUGUGCUGAACAAAAAAUAAAAAUUAUUAUUGAUUUUAUAUUUCAAAAACUCCAUUCUUUCCUAAAUAUUUUCAACAAAGGAUUUCUUUAUGCAUUCUGCCUAAAUACCUAUGCAACUGAGCCCUUCCUUCUCAGCUCAAGAUUCGUCUGGUCUUUCCCUACAGCUUUGUGUGUGCCAUGGCCACAUCUCCUGGGUACAGUUCAAGGAGACAUCUUUUCUAAAAGGGUCUGCGUGAUCAUUAAAAUAUAAUCAAAUGUAUACUGGUGUGUGUGUGCACGUGCGCGUGCGUGUGUCAUGCUAAGGAAGGGGCAAGAAGGAGGAUGCAGAGUGAGUUACAGAGAUCAAGUACUCAAGUGAGUACAGAAAGACUACAGAAGACUUACCUUUAUUUGGUAUUUUAAAUGAAUUCCAUCAGGCUGAGGUCCUGAUUCUAACUAGCUGAAAAAAGUGAAACACUGACAUCUUUUUUGCUGAAAAGCAUUCCCUGAGCUUGAUGCCACAGCAGUUACUGCCCUGUCUCCUGCCCUUCUCAGCCCAGCUUCCUGUAAGGUGGAGGCUGACUUUUCUGUCUCACUUAUUAUUGGCUGAACAUACAGAAUUUGGUCUUCUGCUUCACCAACUUACCUGAAUGUACCCUGGCAAAAGUCACCGUCUACCUGCCAACUGUUAAACCAAUUCAGGUCUUCCAUUCCUGAGCCCAUUUCCUGCAGUUGAUAAAGUUGACCACUCCCUCCUCCUUGGAACUCUUUUCCUCAGUUUCUCUGACAUGGCAGGUCUCUGCUUUGAUUCCUACCUCUCUCUGUUCAUUUGUAGUCUUCACUGUGGGCUCAUCCUACUGGCCUGGAAACCUUAGGGAAAUCUUCCUGGGGUUUUCUCUUGAUCUGGUCAGUGCUCCUCUCACUUUGCAGGCCCUCCUUCAGUGAUGCUCAUGACUCCUAGGCAUCUGUAUCUAUAGCUGUGACCCCAGCCUCCAGCAGUAUCCCUGCACUUAUACAUCCUACUACCUACCUGUGGGUCUAUACUCGAGUCUUGCAGCAGUCAGAAACCCAACAAAUCAAAAAUUGAAGUGAUCAUCCUGUUCUUCUCUCUCUUGCUUCCCUAAACCAACUGUUGUUAUAGUAUAUUCCAUAUCAGCUGAAGACCUGGUCAUCUACCCAAUCACAUAAGCCAUAAAUAGAGGGGUGAAAUUUCAGUUCGCCAUUUUCCCUCACACUACAUCCAGCGUCACCAAGUUCUGUUGAUUUUGCUUUCUAAAUAACUUCAGUUGGCUCCUUUCUUUUCCUGACUCCUAACACAGCCUCAUCUUAUACUCAAAUACAGAAGUGCAGAUAAGGGGUAUCUGGACACAACAUUCCACACCUCUCUCAACUGUCUAGUAUUCAAGAAAAUAGGACUCUGGGUCCACUUUGCAGUCCAGACCUGAUAUGGACCGUUUUACACACAGCCCUGCUUUCCUCUGAGCCUAUCAACGAUCUGCCUUAUUUAAUAUUAACCUAAACUUACCCCAAAUCCUAUAACUCUGCCUUUUCCUUUGUUUGGUGAGAUACCCCAUGGCUCCCCUGGGACGCAGUCUGUCUCAUUGCAAUGGAUCAAUAAACCUAAUUUUAUUACACUACAGGUAUAUUCCUGGAAGUCUUAGACAACUGGGCUAAAACAAAAAUAUUCAACAUCCAUUCUUAAUUAUUAAAUUAGUUACUAAAAUAGGAUAGACAGAUGUUAUUUGGCCAUAAUUUUAUAUACAUGUAAACAAAAGCUAAUACAUACCUAAUGAUGAAGAAACAGAAGCAUUCCUACUAAAGUUAGGAACAUGAAAAAAAUUGAUUACUAUCUAUCUUAUUUUACAGUGUUUUAGAACAGGUGGCCAAUCCAAUUAUACAAGAAAAAUAAGUUAUAAUAUUUAAAGAAAUGCCAAAAUUACUUUUAUUUGUAAGUGAUUAUACACCUAGGAAAUCCAUGAGAACCAAAUAAUAAUAAAGUAUUAUGGCCAGGCGCAGUGGUUCAUGCCUAUAAUCCCAGCAUUUUGGGAGGCUGAGGUGGGUGGAUCACCUGAGGUCAGGAGUUCAAGACCAGCCUGGCCAACAUGGCGAAACCCCAUCUCUUCUAAAAAUACAAAAAUUAGCCUGGUUUGGUGGCACACACCUGUAGUCCCAGCUACUCAGGAGGCUGAAGCAUGAGAAGUGCUUGAUCCUGGGAGGCAGAGGUUGCAGUGAGCCAAGGUCGCACCAGAGCACUCCAGCCUAGUGACAGAGCAAGACUCUGUCUGGAAAAUAAUAAAAAUAAUAAUAAUAGGCAGGGCGUGGUGGCUCACACCUGUAAUCUCAGCACUUUGGGAGGCCAAGUCGGGCGGAUCACCUGAGGUCAGGAGUUCGAGACCAGCUUGACAACAUGGAGAAACUCCAUCUCUACUUAAAAUAAAAAUUAGCCGGGCGUAGUGGUGCAUGCCUGUAAUCCCAGCUACUCGGGAGGCUGAGGCGGGAGAAUUGCUUGAACCUGGGAGGCAGAAGUUGUGGUGAGCCGAGAUCGCACCAUUGCACUCCAGUCUAGACAACAAGAGCAAAACUCUGUCUCAAAAUAAUAAAAAUAAUAAUAAUAAUAAAUAAAGUGGUAAAAGUGGUAAGAUAAAAUUCAGUAAAGUGAAAGGAAAUAUUAAAAUAAAAAAUAACUUUCUUUUAUACAAAUAAUAGUGAGUUAGGACAAUAAUAAUUAACAAGAAUAAAUAAAAUGUAUCAUUUAGUAAAUUAAUAAAAGCUACAUUUAAACCACACUUAUCAAAGUAAAAAAUAAUGUAAAGAAGACAUAUUGCUUUGGAUAGGAAGACUCAGUAUUGUAAAGAUGUCAAUUCUCCCUAAAUUAAUCAAUAUACAAUUUUUUAACUUGACAAAAUGAUACUAAUCCUCAACUAAAAAACAAAAGUGAGACAGAUAAGAAAAAUUCUGAUGAGAGUGGAAGAGCUCUUCCAGCUGUUAAAAUGUAAUGAUAAGCUCCUGAACCUUGGCCUUAGCAAUGAUUUUUUGGCUAUCACAUCAAAAGCCCAGGCCACAAAAGCAAAAAUAAAUAAAUGGGACUACAUCAAGCUGAAAAGCUUCUGCAUAGCAAAGACAACAAGCAACAAAAUGAAAUGGCAACCUAUGGAUUGGAAAAAAUAUUUGCAAACUAUAUAUCUAAUAAGAUACAACAAAUUGAUAAAGAACUCAUACAACUCAAUAGCAGGAAAACAAAUGAUCCCAGUUAAAAAUGGGCAAAAACCUGAAAAGACAUUUCUCCAAGAAGAAAAAUGGCCAAGAUGGAUAUGAAAAGGUGUUCAACAUCACUAAUCAUAAGGGAAAUGUGAAUUGAAACCAUUAUGAGACACUAGAUAAUAAUAGGAUGACUAUUAUCAAAAAGUCAAAAGAUAUUAAUCAUAAACGUGGAUAAGGGUGAAGAGAACAGAAAACCUUUGUGCAUUGUUGGUGAGAAUGUACAGCCAUUGUGGAAAACAGUAUGGAGGUUUCUAAAUAAACUGAAAAUAGGGCUACAUAUGACCCAACAAUCCCUCUUUAGGGGAUAUACACAAAUAAAAUGAGAUAGCCACCUUGUAGAGAUAAAUGUGAUCCCACGUUCAUUGCAGCAUUGCAGCCAAUAUAGGGAAGCAACCUAAAUGCCUGUUGAAGAAUGAAUGGAUAAAGAAACUGUAUACACACACACACACACACAAUGGAAUAUUAUUCAGCCCUAAAAAGAAUAUCUUGCCAUUUGCCACAACAUGGAUGAAACUGGAGGAUAUUAAGUGAAAUAAGGCAGAUACAGAAAGAAAAAUAUUACACGAUUUCACUCACAUGGGGAAUCUAAAGAAAACACUCAAAUACAGGUAUACAGAGAUAACAAAACCUGAGGUGGAGGAGGGUGGAGAGAUGUAGGUCAGAGGAUACAAAGCAGCAGAUAGGAGGGCUAGGCGCAGUGGCUCACUCCUGUAAUCCCAGGACUUUGGGAGGCAGAGGUGGGCAGAUUGCUUGAGUCCAGGAGUUUGAGACCAGCCUAGGCAACAUGACAAAACCCCAUCUCUGCAAAAAAAAAAAAAAAAACAAAAAAAACCCCAAAAAACCAAAACAACAACAAACAAACAAGCAAACAAAACACACACACACAAAAAAAAUUAGCGAGGAGUGCUGGUGCCCACCUGUAGUCCCAGCUACUCAGGAGGAUGGAUUGAGCCUGGGAGGUCGAGGCUGCAGUGAGCAGUGAUUUGAUCGUGCCACUGCACUCCAGCCUGGGGACAGGAGACCCCGUCUCAAACAAAACAAAACCAAGUAGCAGAUAUGCAUGAUGAACAAGCCUAGAGAUCUAAUGUACAACAUAAGGACCACAGUAUAGGUAAUAAAUUCUACUUUAUUUGGGAUUCCUCCUUCACUGUAGUAAUCUUUUUUUAACUAUGUAUGUAUCUCAUAACAUGUUGUAUACCUUAAAUAUAUUCAACGAAGCUUAUUUUAAAAAAUGAAAUGUAUAAUGAUGACUGGAAAGGGUGGUAGUCACAUGGAAAUAAUGAAGCAGAAUAAAAGUUCCAGAUAUUAAAUGCAAAUGAGAAUUUAUUACAUGAUAAAGCUGGCAUUAUACUCGGGGGGGACAGAUAGGCUACUCACUGAAGUGUUUAGAAGCAGAGUAGCUGAAAAUUUUGGCGCAGAAGAAAAUCUCGUGGACCUCCAACUUACCGGUUAAAGUAAAAACUUUCGAAACGUAUAAAGGUUUAAAUAUAAAAUUAAAAUCGUAAAAACAAUUACUAUGUUAACAUAUUUCUUAUAUAGUACUUAGAUUUUCCAACAUUCCACAAACCUAGUAGCAAUUAAGGAAAAUAUUAAUUUCAGAUCAUAUAAAAUUCAGAAGUCCUGUAAGACAAAAAUAGACAAAUAAAAUGUGAAGAUUUUUAAGAAAGAACAAAGGGCUAAUCUAUAUUUUGAAAUCAGUAUAAAAAGACGAACAGAAUUUGAGAUGUGAGCGCGGACAGCUCUGCUGGGCCCUCCAGGCCCUCCGCCCGGUAGAACCCGGAGCCCUGGCCGCGGCUGCCCCACCGGGCCCAUUUCUUGAAGCAGCGGCGAACCACUUUUCCUCCCCGACCUGCCGGCUGCAGGGUCUCCCCGCCCAACCCUGCCAGGCUCAGACGAAGCUUCUGCUGAGCCGCCUGGACGCAGCGCCCCUGGGUGGCGGCAGGUAUAGCAGGGCGGGAAGCAGGGAGGCGGCCCCAACGCCGCGGAGGCCACCAGCGGGUGCAGAGGGCCAGGAAAGCUGGUCUGCGCGCGGCUCAGCUGCCUCCGUAGGCCAUGGAGCCGAGCAGAUCCGGGUCUUCGGGUGGCCGCAAUGUCCCAAGUGGACGACACCCACCUAGUCCCGAGGACAACCGACAAAGUCCUUAAUGGGCCCAGAAGGUGAGGGGAGUCCGGCAAUGAGGGGUGGUAGGGUUAGCGGCCAUCGCCCAGCUCGUCUUCCUUCUACCAGACGCUGGUGCUGGAAAAGAGAAGUGUAAGAAUAACUUGCGCCAUUAGGCCCAUCGGAAAGGCCCACCACCCUUUAGGAAGAUUACUGGCUGUUUAUAGAAGGCCCGUGUAUAUCCUAUGAAGAAGCUGCUCUCAACUUCCCCCCCAGCCUUUUAAAAGAAAACAUUUGCUACAUCGAGCCGUUCUAGGUGUAAAGAGGUUGUGACUUAUGAUAGAGUUAGAAAAUCACACAUCUUGUAAAUUCCCAUUUGUUAAAAAAAUAAUAAUAAUAAUAAUAAUAAUAAUAAUAAUAAUAGGACAUAAAUGGCUUCUGGAGAUGACUUUUUGCAAUGAAGUUGUUAGACCACCUCUGGAAGUGACAGCAGGAGCCACACAUCCACGUUUAUUAAGUGAGUUAGAGCAGGAGUCCCCAACCCCUGGAUCUAGGUUGCACGCUCCUUAUGAGACUCUAAUAAUGCCUGAUGAUCUGAGGUGGAACAGUUUCAUCCUGAAACCAUGCCCCUACCUUCCAUGGAAAAAUUGCCUUCCGUGAAACCAUUCCCUGGUGCCAAAGAGGUUGGGGACCACUGGGUUAGAGGACAUGGGGCAGAAGACCUGAGAAGGAAGAGAGGACAGUUCUGUGCCACACUGGUCAUAUUUAGAAGACAUUUUCAUAUUCCAACCAUUGUUCUGUGUGUGCAUUUUAUUUCUCACGACUGUAUAUGUAGUUAACAAUACUAUUUUUUAGGGAGGUGGGGGGGUCAGCCCCCCGCCUGGCCAGCCGCCCCGUCCGGGAGGGAGGUGGGGGGGUCAGCCCCCCGCCCGGCCAGCCGCCCCGUCUGGGAGGUGAGGGGCGCCUCUGCCCGGCCGCCCCUACUGGGAAGUGAGGAGCCCCUCUGCCAGGCCAGCCGCCCCGUCCGGGAGGGAGGUGGGGGGGUCAGCCCCCCGCCCGGCCAGCCGCCCUGUCCGGGAGGGAGGUGGGGGGGUCAGCCCUCCGCCCGGCCAGCCGCCCCGUCUGGGAGGUGAGGGGCGCCUCUGCCCGGCCGCCCCUACUGGGAAGUGAGGAGCCCCUCUGCCCGGCCAGCCGCCCCGUCCGGGAGGGAGGUGGGGGGGUCGGCCCCCCGCCCGACCAGCCGCCCCAUCCGGGAGGGAGGUGGGGGGGUCAGCCCCCCGCCCGGCCAGCCGCCCUGUCCGGGAGGGAGGUGGGGGUGUCAGCCCCACGCCCGGCCAGCCGCCUCGUCCGGGAGGGAGGUGGGGGGGUCAGCCCCCCGCCCGGCCAGCCGCCCCGUCCGGGAGGGAGGUGGGGGGGGUCAGCCCCCCUGCCCGGCCAGUGGCCCCGUCCGGGAGGUGAGGGGCGCCUCUGCCCGGCUGCCCCUACUGGGAAGUGAGGAGCCCCUCUGCCCGGCCAGCCGCCCGUCCGGGAGGGAGAGUGGGGGGUCAGCCCCCCCCCGCCCGGCCAGCCGCCCUGUCCGGGAGGUGAGGGGCGCCUCUGCCCAGCCACCACCCGGUCUGGGAGGUGUGCCCAACAGCUCAUUGAGAACGGGCCAGGAUGACAAUGGCGGCCUUGUGGAAUAGAAAGGCGGGAAAGGCGGGGAAAAGAUUGAGAAAUCGGAUGGUUGCCGUGUCUGUGUAGAAAGAAGUAGACAUGGGAGACUUUUCAUUUUGUUCUGCACUAAGAAAAAUUCCUCUGUCUUGGGAUCCUGUUGAUCUGUGACCUUACCCCCAACCCUGUGCUCUCUGAAACAUGUGCUGUGUCCACUCAGGGUUAAAUGGAUUAAGGGCGGUGCAAGAUGUGCUUUGUUAAACAGAUGCUUGAAGGCAGCAUGCUCGUUAAGAGUCAUCGCCAAUCCCUAAUCUCAAGUAAUCAGGGACACAAACACUGCGGAAGGCCGCAGGGUCCUCUGCCUAGGAAAACCAGAGACCUUUGUUCACUUGUUUAUCUGCUGACCUUCCCUCCACUAUUGUCCCAUGACCCUGCCAAAUCCCCCUCUGUGAGAAACACCCAAGAAUUAUCAAUAAAAAAAUAAAUUAAAAAAAAAAAAAAAAAACAAUACUAUUUUUUGAACUAUCUACCCUUUCUAGAUGUUCUGAAAUGCCUAUGUUAAAAUUAGAGAUAGUAAAAUAACACAUUUUGUAAAUCUUUUUGUUAAAAUUCAUAUGUAAUGUUGUUUUGGUUGGGGGGGGUGGCCAAACCACCUGUUAAUAAUACACAUUGUGUUUGUGCACUGGUUCAGGGGAGGAGAGAGGAAAGGAAGUGUAAGAGCUCUAUGCCAAUGUGCUUAUAGUGAGGCAAGGUUAACCAUUGUCUCAUGCCUGGGCAUUUUGUUUUACUUAUCUGGGUAUAUUGUGGAUCUAAAGGACAAAUGAGUCCUGACUUUACAUCUAGUCUUUCUAGAUGUUAAAGAGGUUGCUAGUGUAUGACAAAAGUAGUUAGUAAACUAAUAUAUUUUGUACAUUUCGUUUUAAGAUUCCCAGGAAAGACAGUCUUCUGAAAAUUUGAGCAUUAUUGCCCAGUGGGUUGAUGGAGAUGGGAAGGUGUAGGCCAGAAUGUUCAUACUUGGAAGACUCAGUCAUAACUGUUUUUACAUGUGUUCACUUUAUUCAAGACUUCUGUGCAUAUAGUGGACGAAUUAACUUCUUACCUGAAACAUCUUAUCUAUGUAGAUGUUCAGAAUUGCCUGAUGUAUGUUAAGUGUAGAGGUAGUAAAAUAUCACCUUGUAAAUAUCUUUUUGCUAAAAUUCUUGGGAAGUACUGUCUUUUGGAAGUGGAAUUGUGAAGCCACCUCUGUAAGCAGUAUAGUACUGUCUAUACUUGUUCAAUGGUUUAGAAAUGGGAGGGAAGAAAUUGCCAAAGGUAAUAUGCUAGUGUGUUCAUACUUGGACAUUUCACUUGCCAUUUUUCUGUCUGUUUUGUGCAUUUUGUUUUGCUGUGUAUGUAGAGUACAUAAUGGACAAAUGAGUCCUAAUUUUGCAACAUUUGGUCUCUAGAUGUUUAAGAAGUUGCCAGUGUAUGACAAAGUAUCUAGUAAAAUUAGCACAUUUUGCACACUUUGUAUUGAAAUUCAUAGGAAAGCUUGUCUUCUGUAAAUGAUUUUUGGGUAUGAAUUUGUUCAGCCAUCUCUAAGCGUUACACAUGCCUGUACCUGUCCACUGGAUUGAAGACAGAGAGAAGGGAGUGAGGAAGGACUGGUUCAAGGUCAAAAUUGUCAUAUUUAGAAGAUACCUCCGAUUAUAGCCACUGAUACAUGUGCAAUUUUAUUUUACAGUGCUAUGUACACAGUGGAAAGUUAUAUGAAAUAUCUGGUCUCUCUAGAUAGUUAGAAAUGCUUGAUGUAUUUAAAAGUAGAAAUAGUAUAAUAACACUUUUUGUAAAUAGCUUUUAAAAACUGAUGGGAAAUACUGUGUUUGCAAGUGGGAUUGUUAAAUCACCUCUGUGAACAGUGUUACUUGUUCAUUCAGUUGAGGAAGGUGAGAGGGAAGAAAUUACAAAAGAUGUUUUGCUAUUGUGUACUAGAAAAUUUCAGUUUAUCCAUUGCCUUAUAUGUUAAAUGCAUUGCAAGUAACUUUGCUAUACUACAUAUUGUGUUAUAUACUGGAAAAAUGAGUCCUAAUUUUAAAAUAUCCACUCUCUAGAUACUAAAGAGGUUGCCAAUGUAUGACAAAAAUAGUAAAGUAACACAUUUUGUACACUUUGUGUUAACGUUUAUAAAAAGACUAUCUUCUGAAAACGACUUUUGGAAGUGAAAUGAUAACAUCAACCCUAAGUGACACAUGGGCCCAUAUCCACCAGGUUGGUGGUGCAGAGGAGCUGGAAGAAAUGAAGGAUUCUAGAUCAGAAUAUUCCUAUUUAGAAGACAGUUUAAGAUAAACCAUGUGUGUAGUUUAUUCAACCCUACUGAUGCAAGAGAAUAGGGUCUGGAGGCAGGAAACAUAAAGCAGAUUCAUGCAGACUUCCUAGAAAUAAAUGAAAUGGAAACACAUCAGCUAUGACAGGACAUAUACUCUCCAACAGAGUAAAUGACUUUGUAACUUUAUUUCAUCCUCUCCAUUUACAUAGGGCGUACAUCAAGUAAAUGACUAGGGUGUAUACUAAGUAAAUGACUUUGUAACUUUAUUUCAUCCUCUUCAUUUACAUAAGGCAUAUACCAAGUAACCAAUGGAAACCUUGAGAGGGUAUUUAAACCCGAGAAAAUUCUGUAACUGGGCUCUUGAGCCCCUAAGCACAGGCCUUCUCCCACCCUGUGGAGCGUACUUUCAUUUCAUAAAUCUCUGCUUUUGUUGUUUCAUUCUUUCCUUGCUUUGUGUGUUUUGUCCAAUUCUUGGUUCAAUAUGCCCAGAACCUGGACACCCUCCACUGGUAACAUAUUUUGGCAAGGCAGCCAGGAGGUAAGCCCAAAGUUUGGGAUUUUUCAUCUUUUCUUUUCCACUCCAUACAGGGGAAUCUCUCCCUCUGUCUCUUUUUCCUUUCCAACUCGGGACCCUUGGUGGGCAGCGCCUAAACACGGAGGCAACCGCAGGUUUCUGGGUGGGGCCAUCCUGAAGGACUUUUUUCUAUCUUUUCUGGUUGUGGUCCCUGAUUCCUAUGUGUGGCGCAGCUCAGGGCAAACUUGCAGCUCAGGGUGAACUUGCAUGUGUUUCAGGCGACGGAAACCCUACUUGACUGGCUAAGGACAAAAGAAGCCUACUCAGCUUCCAUUUCCUAUCAUUACAGUUCAUGGCUAUCAUGCUAGUGGAACAGGAAGCAUGGGAUAAUGUGGCCUUAUCAAAUUAUAAGGAUGCUAAACGCCAGUGAUUACACCCAGGAACCAAAGGACAGCUCACAAUUGCCUCUGGAGGGAAAAUAUGCAAAGCGGCACUGGUGCCCACGUAAGGUCAGAGAUGCCUGACACUCUUAAGACUGGACCCCAAAGGGGGAUUCCCCAGGGGAUCCUCCAGACUUCAACCUCUCCAAAGGGGAUGCCCUUGGCAGCAGUUCUAAGGACUAGUACUAAGCCCUCCUUAGAAUUUUCUCUUGCAGUUGCAAUACUGUUUGGCCCCAAUAUGGUUUGGAUUCUGGCAUUUGCUGUUGAAUGGGAAAGCGGGAUGCAGUUGCAUGUAUCCAGGCUUUGGUGCUGCUGUUCUAAGCAGGGGCAGGCCUAGUUAUUAUGUGAUGUUCUCCUUUGGUGCUGUUUGACCCCAGUGUUCUUUCGAGUCUGGGGAGGUUUGGCCUUUAAAAAUCAAACUGCCAUGGAAAUUGCUUUACCUGAAAUAAUAGUUCACAGCCUUCAUUGGAUUGCUUAUUGGGUACACAAAGUAAAAUUGGCAAGCUUGUAUUGCUAUCUCAUGGUUAGGGUUCCAAGGUAAAAGCUAUUGAAUCUUCAUUUGUGUGUGUGUAUACACAUGUCUAGAUGUGUUUAUUUGCACAUUUGUUAUAUGUUGUGUUUUGGCAUAUAAGUAAAAGAGCACUCAUAAAUUAAGUAAAUAAGUCGAAGCAAUUUUCAAGUUCACAUGACUUAAGUAUAACUUUCCUAAACAGGCUAGUUUUAAAAUUAUUGGUGAAGUAAAAAUAGAAAUGCCUUCAGAAUUGUCAGCAUAUAUUUUUGUCUGGGUUUUAUAUUUGUCUCUGCUAGAUAUUUUGAGGUGUUAGGGUUUGGCAUAGAAGGUUAUAAAACUAUAAACCCAGCCAAAACAAAACGAUCUCGUUUGCGUUUUUUUUUUUUUUUUUUUUUUUUUUUUUGACAAAUGAGCAUAAUUUAAUGUUAGCUAAAUCUUCUGGGUUACUGGCAAAAAUACGUAUGUAUUAACUUUGAGGCUCUUACUUAGGUUUAAGUGCACACCUGGCUAUUCAAAAUGUGGUUAACAGGGAAAUAACUGACUUUAAAAGAUAGUGUCUAACAUUUCGGUUUACAGAGGUAAUCUAGAUAAACUGUUAAAAGUGAAACAAUUGAGUACAGUGAAUGGGACAAAUGUUUUAGAUAAGCUUUUUGUGUAAAGUCUUAAAAUCAUUUUUGAUGCUCAUUUAAGAUCUGGGCCAUUUCCAAUUAGAAAGGUUGUGAUAUGGGGAAAUAUGUUUCUAAAAUUGUGGAAUUGUUCUUAACUAUAAAUUCCCAUAUCUGAUAGUUCAGGAUUUCUAGCUUUUUAGCGUUUCACUAAAGUUUUAGGUUACUAAGGAUAAGAAUUCUAGUUAACACAUAAUUCUGUAUACAAAACAUGCCAGAAAGUUUGUGUUAUUAGUGAGAAAAAGAAUAAUUUAGAAGUUAUCUAAAAGUUAGUUCAAAUUACAGAUUUGAAAAGGUUACUUAUGAAACAAUGUAGUAAGGAACCAGUAAGUAGAGGAGAACGAUAUGGAAAAAGUUUAGAUAAUAAAAUAUUCUUUAAAACCUGAUAGAGAAUUGGAGAUAUUUGGCUAAUUAACAUUUUCAUAGUGAAAGCUGUUAGUCUUGAUAAAAGUAAAAUAAGCAUUGUAAAGAAAUGCAUCGGCAGUUUGGCAAUUCCUUUUUACUAUAGUUAAGCAUGAAGCCGGAUUUGGUGUGGAGCCAAAUUUCACAUACAUGCUUGCAUUGCUUCACACUGUUUACUGUUUUGUGUGGAUAGUGCUGGCACUGGAGUACUUAUUGGUUAUGUGCCUAUAGUGUAUUUCUUGAUUGCACAGGAUGUAUGGUGAUAUUGGUGAACUUAAGGAUACUGAAUUGUGUAUCAGGAACAAAAUAUUCAUUAUGUGGGUUUUGGGGGGCCCUAGGUAAACACUGUAGCCUCCAGGGUAGAUUGAGAAGGAAAAAUUUAGGGUUGGGUUCCUAUUUGUUUUUGCUUCUAAUUUUCAUUUGUUUGCCAUUUAUUCUCCUCUGGCUUUGCUUGUGUAUGCACAUAUAAAAUCAUAUAUAUUUUUUUUAAAUUUCUAGUGGAAGGCUUUUAUUUGGUUCUGUGAAUAGUUAUUUUGUUCCCUAUGCAUUUCUAGCAAGUCAUCAUUUGUUCCAUUUAUCUGGAAUUCCUAGGCUACCUUUGUCAGGCUGGCAGGAAUUGAUGGAGCACACCAGCUUUUUAACCUUGAACUAACUCAAAUUCUGUUUAUGAUACUUUAAGUGUGUUGAGUAUAUUUUCAUAAACAGAAUUUGAGUCAUAUUUCUCUGUCUGCCCAUUUUCUCCAAAAUUCGUAAACUAUUUGUGAAUAUUCUUAAUUCAUGGCAAUGUGUUUGUUUGCAUAUAGUCAAGCAGGGUUCCUAGGGCUGCUUUGGGAGACAGAACCCAGAAACCUGGCAUACUGGCAAAAGGGUAAGAAUUUCUUACCAGCCAGACUCUGGUCUCUGUCUCUCUGUGCAAACUGCAUAAAUGAAUAGUAAAAGUCACUGUUUAUCUCCUCUGUAAAGUUUUGAUUAAUAUAAAAAAAGAAUUCUGAGGCCGAUCUUAAGCUGUAGUGAAUCUGGUGUGCUUUGUGUCUUUCUGUAUUGUUUUGUCAUAAAGAGGGGUACCUUAGAAUAAAAUGUGUGCUUAGGACCCCAUAGACCUGCUGUUCAAGACACACCAGCAGACUGGUCAGUCAUGUCUUUGGGAGCUUGACCUUGUAACCAUGUGGCCAUGCUUUCUCUUUUCACAGUGGCAGCCUGGGUUUAGGGUUCAAUUCCUGGCUUAGGGAAUGAGUCCUUUAUCUUCUGUCUGUGUAUUUAUAUGUGUUGUGUGUGUACUAUAAAAGAGCAUUAAUUAAUUAGCUUAAUAAUAAUAAGAGCUUAAAUCAAAUAUUUUAUCAGAAAAGUAAAAAAUGUAAUGCCUUCUAUUUACUUCAUGUAACUUAAGUAAUCUUUGGGAAAUAAAGACAGUUUUAAAGAUUAUUGGUAAAAUAAAAAUAUCUUCAAAAUGUAAAUAUUUAGUCUAAAUUAUGCAGGUCAGAUAUUAGAUUUGCAAAAUGCUUUAAGGUCAUAAACCGCUUCUUUGACUUUUAAAAAUUGCUCAAUUUAUUUUGGAGCAUUAGAUUCUAGAUAAGGCCUGGGGACAAAUAGAAUUAGCCAUGUCCCCUAGCUAUGCAAAGAAGGUUAUAAAGAAAGGAGAUUUUAUAUAAGAAAGGAUCUUAUAUCGUAAAUUCGUGUCCUAAAGUAAAAUAAGCGGUUGUUAAAAAAGAGGGAUGUUUAGGACAAGUUAGAAAGUCAAAGCAUGUCGUAGAUGGUCUGUGUAAGUCAUGAAAUAAUUUACAAAAGAGAAUUUAUGCAAGAAAUAUACAAUUUAACGGUGAUUAGACCUCCUAAAUGCUUCAUAAAAUGCCACUAUGACUCUUAACUCUACAACUUGCCUGCUUUACAGCUCGGUAAGGCCUGAGACACGUGGAGUCAGAUGCUGGAGUCAGACCUUAAGUGUACUUCUCUCUGGGUCCUAGACUCCACAACUAAUAUAUAAUUAAAAUCCUUAACUUACCAAAGUUUUCACCAAAAGUAAAACUCGCUAAGAGUUAACAUUGUAACAUGUAAGUGAGACUACUGAAGCAACAGUUUUACAUGCAAGUUACGUAAGAAAAGUGAAUGCAUUUUCAGUGAAAGAUUAUAACAAGGCAUGGGAAUGUAGAUUUUUUUUUCUGUCUAAAGGGUUAAAGGAUUGUUUUAAGUUAGGAUAAAGCUAAAAGUUUGAAUGAGUUGUGGAAGAUUUAUAAAAAUUAAUAUUGUAAAAAAUUAUGUGUGUGAACAUAUUGACUAAAUUUAAAGGGGUAUUUUCUGGUUUUUCCAUAAAUUGAACAUCAAAAUAAAAGCACAAACAGGGUUUUCUUAAAGCACCGAUCUGCUCUUUAACAAACAUUUGUAAAGGAUUAUAAAAGGUUUAUGAGAAUCUCACCUUAUGGUCAAACGGAUUAAGAUUGGAAAGAUAUGUCUACAAGGUUUUCUUAAAAAUUGGGGUUGACAUUAAUAGCACACUAAUGCAAGGGUGAAAUUUGGCUUUCUCUCUUGAACAAGAUUUUCAUGCAGUAUUAAAAGAUAAUGAAAGAUCUUUGUUUGCCUUUUGAAUAAACUACCCCCCCACCAAAAAAAAGGAAGGGAAAGACAAGAGACAGAUUGUUUGUAAAGUAAGUCUUCCAUCUAUCAACAUGGAAAGGUUUUUGCCUUUUAAAACAUUUUUGAGUCAUCAUUUUGCUAAAUGAAUGACUAUGGUAACCUGGAAUUCCAUUUCAUAAUGUCAAGUGUUUUAAAUCUUUAACAUAUUUAAUAGGCUUCCCAAAAUCAAAUUUCAGCUUCAAAAUUGUCUUUUCUAACCUCUAACUUUGAGAUGCUGCAGAGGGCCCCUGAAGCAUCCAAAAGAGAGGUAAACAGAAUUAUUUGACAUGUUUAAUUACAUGGGAAGCAUUGUCAAAAAGAAAAAAAUUUAAUCUUCUUCAGGUUAUAUUUUAGUGAAUAAUAUUAAUAUAUGUUCCAAAAUUGUAUGAGAUUUCUAAAAUUCCAAUAUGUCUGAGUAUAUGCUAUCAAUCAUAAUUAUGAUUAUUAUGUUAUUGUAGACCACAGAAAUAACCAAAUUUCCUUGUCAAUUGUGUUUUUAACUAUAACUAUUUAAAGUCAUUUCCACAGUUAAUUGCUUAAUGCUGAUGCAGUUUCUGAAAACUUCACAAGCAUGCAAAGUCCUAGAAUAUGGUGUCUUUUAGGAGAUUCAUGAAAGAUUGGAAAGGACCCUAAAAAGCACUCUUGAAUACAGGUUUCUAAUAAGUUUAGAAUUAUAUCAUUUGAACUGGGUAAGAAUUCCUGGAACUUUAAUGAAAAGACUGACUGAGUUCUAAAACUGCUAACCCAAGUAGAACAAAAAUUAAUUAAAUACCAAGAAAAUACUUUGCCAGAUUUUCAUGCUAAAUCAGCUGAUACUGAAACUGUUUAGAUAUAAAAUUUGAAUAAACUCCAUCAUUUAAAUCAAAUUACCUAUGAUAACCCAUCAGUUAUCAGUGUUAUGCACCUAAUUUGGGGAAACAACUGGUAUUCAAGAGGAUAUGAGUCUAAUGUUAAUUAAGCAUGAACUCAUGGAGAACCAGGAUGGCCACCUUGUCCUUCCUAAGUCGUUAAAGCUUUUGUUAGUAAAAUUUCUGCAUUACAUGACUCGUCACGGAAAAGAUAAAAUGAUCCAAAUUGAAUAUAUUGAUGUGGUGACUUAUAAAUUGCUAAAAUAGUUUAUAACCAAUGUUUGGUCCCAUAUUCCUGGGAAAACAAUCAAAGCUUCAGGUACAUCCAGUCACCUGAUAGGCCAUUUAAACAUUUUAUAGAGGGAUUUUAUUCAAUUGUUAUUUUCAGUGCAUGUUUUCUGGUUGUAUAAAAGCUUUCCCAUGCAAGAGGGCUGAUGUUAUAACACUAAGUUAUUAUGCCACCAAGUAUUUUCACAAGGUAAAGAAAGCUUUUUAUGGUUCACUGAGGACAAUCAACUCCUUCACAACCUAGAAACUGAAGAUUGUAUCUUCUGAAAACAUUGGAUAAAGACUGUCCUUGCCAUCCACACUACAGCAAAACUUCUGGACUUUGAACUUUGGGUUCAUGAUCUCACAACUGAGAAGAGUCCCUCCACACUCUUGGAACUGUACACCCAUUGGAACCCUUAAGGUAAAGCUAACCAGGGAAGUUUCUCUCCCGAAGAAGAUGGCAUCCUUGAUGUGAACAGCUUUUCCCAAGAUCAUGAAUCAAGACUUCUCUAUUAUCAUGAGACUCUUAUCUUUGAAUAUUUUUUCCUUGCUUUUGCCUCUAUGAAGAAUAGAAGUGGAAAAAGGAUCUGUUGUGUACAAUUAUGGGUUAUACUUUUAUUUGUGAAGAAUUUUGCAGCCAGCUUUAGGUCCUUUUUCCAUGAUUUGGAAUAAAAGAGGCAAAUGUAUCCCUCAUAAUAGGCUCCAUAGCAGUUUACUGUAAAGGCUAUGGUUACAUAAUAGACUAAAUUAUCUUAAGAAAGUUAUGCUAAAUAAUAGAGUUGGCUAAACAGAAGAGUAUCUGUGCAGCUGCUGGCACUCAUGGCCUAUGGAGAAAACAUCAGGUAUUAUAGAGAUUCAGUUGUAGCAAAUUAAUGAAGAGACUGCUUAGUUAAGUGAGUAGACUCUUUAGCUCAUUGUUUAAUCUAUUUGAGUUUAGGAGGUUUGGUUUAUGGUGACCCUGGAUAAGGAGCAUACUUACUCUCAACUCUUGGUAUUAUCCUCCUGAUAGUCAUAAUAAUAGUCUCCCUGGUGUGCUGUAUUCUCUCAACGGUUUUAAAUGUUUGCAUGCUGCCACCUCUAGAAUGUCAAAUGGCCUCUCUUCAACUGGAAUGACAAGAGCUGAAAGAAAUUGCAGCCAUGAGGACACUGUAACCUACGAAUGAUGUGCUGAGUCCAAAAGCCCAAAGUGUUGGUAACUGAGAGUGGUGCUAAGUAAGGCCCUAAGUUUUGGUCACACUCUCACUUAAGUGAGAACCUGACCAAAAAAGUGGAAUUUUUUUUUUUUUUUUUUUUUUUGAGAUGGAGUCUCACUCUGUCACCCGGGCUGGAGUGCAGUGGCACGAUCUCGGCUCACUGCAAGCUCCACUUCCCGGGUUCACGCCAUUUUUCUGUCUCAGCCUCCCGAGUAGCUGGGACUACAGGCACCUGCCACCACGCCCGGCUAAUUUUUUUGUAUUUUUAGUGGAGACGGGGUUUCACCAUGUUAGCCAGGAUGGUCUCGAUCUCCUAACCUCAUGAUCUGCCCACCUCGGCCUCCCAAAGUGCUGGGAUAACAGGCGUGAGCCACUGCACCUGGCCAAAAAGGGGAAUUUUUUUUAAACAAAAUUAUGGGAGGUCAUUUUUUUGUACUGAGCCCAUGCGCCAGGCCCCAACAGACCAAACUAAACCAAAACGGAGUCACGUAUGCCAAGACCUUAAGGAAACACAUAGAUCCUAGAACAGACCACAGGCCAGGUUUUGUUUUUCUCCUACAAAUCUCUAUAACAAACAUUCCUGACAGCAUAGAUAUCCACCCCCUGAGUUCCCAUUAAAUCUUUUAACCAAAUUAAUUUCCUCUCGCCAAAAGACCAUCAAGCUUCAGAUGAUCAUGCAACAAAAGUUUCAUCCAGUUCCACCACCCCUGGCCAUCAAGGAGCUACCCUGCCUUCACUAGAAAGAGCAGAGCAGGACUUCUGUGAUCCUCAAUAGGUAGGGACUAGGCCUCAAGCCAACAUGAAGCAGUUACAAAAGAAAGACCAUCGGCCCCUCCACCUCCCAUAAAGAUUUAUGGGGAUCCCAUCUCUGGAGGGAAAUGAGGCAGAAGAAUAGGGUCUGUAGGCAAGGAAUAUAAGGCAGAUGCAUGCUCACUUCCUAGAACUAAAUCAAAUGGAAACACUUCAGCUAUGAUGGGAAAUGUCUUCUGUAUUUACAUAGGGCAUACACUGAGUAACCAAUGGAAACCUCUAGAGGGUAUUUAAACCCCAGAAAAUUCUGUAACCGGGCUAUUGAGCCCCUAUGCUCAAGCCCUCUGCCACCCUGUGGAGUGUACUUUUGUUUUCAAUAAACCUCUGCUUUUGUUGCUUCA